CAUUUGACAAGCAGGACAACGAAGAGGCAGAAGGAUCUGGGCCUGUGCGCGACGCCCCGGGGGACGAGGCUCAUGGAGAAGUUUCGGGCGGUGCUGGACCUGCACGUCAAGCACCACAGCGCCUUGGGCUACGGCCUGGUGACCCUGCUGACGGCGGGCGGGGAGCGCAUCUUCUCCGCCGUGGCAUUCCAGUGCCCGUGCAGCGCCGCCUGGAACCUGCCCUACGGCCUGGUCUUCUUGCUGGUGCCGGCGCUCGCGCUCUUCCUCCUGGGCUACGUGCUGAGCGCACGCACGUGGCGCCUGCUCACCGGAUGCUGCUCCAGCGCCCGCGCGAGUUGCGGAUCGGCGCUGCGCGGCUCCCUGGUGUGCACGCAAAUCAGCGCGGCCGCCGCGCUCGCGCCCCUCACCUGGGUGGCCGUGGCGCUGCUCGGGGGCGCCUUUUACGAGUGCGCGGCCACCGGGAGCGCGGCCUUCGCGCAGCGCCUGUGCCUCGGCCGCAACCGCAGCUGCGCCGCGGAGCUGCCGCUGGUGCCGUGCAACCAGGCCAAGGCGUCGGACGUGCAGGACCUCCUGAAGGAUCUGAAGGCUCAGUCGCAGGUCUGCCGCUGGCGCUGGGGGCGUUUGGGAGGAGCCGAGAGGCCGAGCUUUCUCAGGGCCGCUGGGGUGUUGGGCUGGAUCUUGAUAGCAGUUGUUAUCAUCAUUCUUCUGAUUUUUACAUCUGUCACCCGAUGCCUAUCUCCAGUUAGUUUUCUGCAGCUGAAAUUCUGGAAAAUCUAUUUGGAACAGGAGCAGCAGAUCCUUAAAAGUAAAGCCACAGAGCAUGCAACUGAAUUGGCAAAAGAGAAUAUUAAAUGUUUCUUUGAGGGCUCGCAUCCAAAAGAAUAUAACACUCCAAGCAUGAAAGAGUGGCAGCAAAUUUCAUCACUGUAUACUUUCAAUCCGAAGGGCCAGUACUACAGCAUGUUGCACAAAUAUGUCAACAGAAAAGAGAAGACUCACAGUAUCAGGUCUACUGAAGGAGAUACGGUGAUUCCUGUUCUUGGCUUUGUAGAUUCAUCUGGUAUAAACAGCACUCCUGAGUUAUGACCUUUUGAAUGAGUAGAAAAAAAAAUUGUUUUGAAUUAUUGCUUUAUUAAAAAAUAAACAUUGGUA